CCCAAAUGGACACUACCAUGGAAGCUGACCUGGGUGCCACUGGCCACAGGCCCCGCACAGAGCUUGAUGAUGAGGACUCCUACCCCCAAGGUGGCUGGGACACGGUCUUCCUGGUGGCCCUGCUGCUCCUUGGGCUGCCAGCCAAUGGGUUGAUGGCGUGGCUGGCCGGCUCCCAGGCCCGGCAUGGAGCUGGCACGCGUCUGGCGCUGCUCCUGCUCAGCCUGGCCCUCUCUGACUUCUUGUUCCUGGCAGCAGCGGCCUUCCAGAUCCUAGAGAUCCGGCAUGGGGGACACUGGCCGCUGGGGACAGCUGCCUGCCGCUUCUACUACUUCCUAUGGGGCGUGUCCUACUCCUCCGGCCUCUUCCUGCUGGCCGCCCUCAGCCUCGACCGCUGCCUGCUGGCGCUGUGCCCACACUGGUACCCUGGGCACCGCCCAGUCCGCCUGCCCCUCUGGGUCUGCGCCGGUGUCUGGGUGCUGGCCACACUCUUCAGCGUGCCCUGGCUGGUCUUCCCCGAGGCUGCCGUCUGGUGGUACGACCUGGUCAUCUGCCUGGACUUCUGGGACAGCGAGGAGCUGUCGCUGAGGAUGCUGGAGGUCCUGGGGGGCUUCCUGCCUUUCCUCCUGCUGCUCGUCUGCCACGUGCUCACCCAGGCCACAGCCUGUCGCACCUGCCACCGCCAACAGCAGCCCGCAGCCUGCCGGGGCUUCGCCCGUGUGGCCAGGACCAUUCUGUCAGCCUAUGUGGUCCUGAGGCUGCCCUACCAGCUGGCCCAGCUGCUCUACCUGGCCUUCCUGUGGGACGUCUACUCUGGCUACCUGCUCUGGGAGGCCCUGGUCUACUCCGACUACCUGAUCCUACUCAACAGCUGCCUCAGCCCCUUCCUCUGCCUCAUGGCCAGUGCCGACCUCCGGACCCUGCUGCGCUCCGUGCUCUCGUCCUUCGCGGCAGCUCUCUGCGAGGAGCGGCCGGGCAGCUUCACGCCCACUGAGCCACAGACCCAGCUAGAUUCUGAGGGUCCAACUCUGCCAGAGCCGAUGGCAGAGGCCCAGUCACAGAUGGAUCCUGUGGCCCAGCCUCAGGUGAACCCCACACUCCAGCCACGAUCGGAUCCCACAGCUCAGCCACAGCUGAACCCUACGGCCCAGCCACAGUCGGAUCCCACAGCCCAGCCACAGCUGAACCUCAUGGCCCAGCCACAGUCAGAUUCUGUGGCCCAGCCACAGGCAGACACUAACGUCCAGACCCCUGCACCUGCUGCCAGUUCUGUGCCCAGUCCCUGUGAUGAAGCUUCCCCAACCCCAUCCUCGCAUCCUACCCCAGGGGCCCUUGAGGACCCAGCCACACCUCCUGCCUCUGAAGGAGAAAGCCCCAGCAGCACCCCGCCAGAGGCGGCCCCGGGCGCAGGCCCCACGUGAGGGUCCAGGAA